GACAACGAGCGACUGGGCGGCGGAGGACGAGGAGGAGGAAGAGGAGGCCGAGCAACAAGAUGGCCCCUGCUGCAGGAGCAGCCUCAGCAGCAGCAGGUGGGAGGCCGGAGGCGGUGCUGGCGGUGGCGGCGGCAGCCGUGGCCCGGCGGCCUGGGACAGAAUCAGAGUCAACGGUGGCCUCGGCGGCGGCGGCGGCUGCCGCGGCGGUGGCGACGGCCGCGGGGACUCGGAGCUGAGAGGAGCUGCUGCUCGGACCAGCGCGGUUAUAUUUCACACUAUGUGCUGACUGUAUCUACAGAAGAUAUUUAAAAAAAAAAAAGAUAAACUUUUUUUCAAAGAUUUUGAUUCCAGUGGAAUCUUUGCUUUAGAUUUGUGUGUGUGUUUGUGUUCGUGAAUUGUAACUCCAGAAGCAAUGCCUGUACAAGCUCCACAAUGGACGGAUUUCCUCUCCUGCCCAAUUUGCACUCAGACUUUCGACGAAACAAUUCGAAAGCCCAUCAGUUUGGGUUGUGGCCAUACUGUCUGCAAGAUGUGCCUGAAUAAACUCCACCGCAAGGCUUGCCCAUUUGACCAGACCACUAUCAAUACAGACAUUGAGCUCCUCCCUGUGAACUCAGCAUUGCUGCAGCUCGUGGGUGCUCAGGUCCCUGAGCAGCAGCCUAUUACUUUGUGUAGUGGGGUUGAAGACACAAAGCAUUAUGAGGAAGCCAAGAAAUGUGUAGAAGAAUUAGCAUUGUACUUAAAACCGCUCAGCAGUGCUAGAGGAGUGGGUCUGAACAGCACUACUCAGAGUGUUCUGAGUCGCCCAAUGCAGAGGAAGCUUGUGACUCUAGUCCACUGUCAACUAGUAGAAGAAGAAGGCAGGAUUCGUGCCAUGAGGGCAGCUCGAUCUUUAGGUGAACGAACAGUUACAGAGCUCAUUCUCCAGCACCAGAAUCCUCAGCAACUCUCUUCCAAUCUUUGGGCAGCAGUAAGGGCUAGGGGAUGCCAGUUCCUUGGACCAGCAAUGCAGGAGGAAGCUUUAAAGUUGGUUCUGCUGGCCUUAGAAGAUGGUUCUGCUUUGUCAAGAAAAGUAUUGGUUCUGUUUGUGGUGCAAAGAUUGGAGCCACGGUUUCCUCAAGCCUCUAAAACUAGCAUUGGGCAUGUUGUUCAGCUCCUUUAUAGAGCCUCCUGUUUCAAGGUCACCAAACGUGAUGAAGACUCUUCUUUGAUGCAGCUGAAAGAAGAAUUUAGAACCUAUGAAGCUCUGCGGCGAGAACAUGACUCCCAGAUAGUGCAGAUUGCUAUGGAAGCAGGCUUACGAAUUGCACCGGACCAGUGGUCCUCUUUGCUUUAUGGAGACCAGUCUCACAAAUCUCAUAUGCAGUCCAUUAUUGACAAGUUGCAGACUCCAGCCUCUUUUGCACAGAGUGUUCAGGAACUAACAAUUGCUCUCCAGCGAACUGGAGACCCAGCAAACUUGAACCGACUAAGACCCCAUUUGGAGCUGUUAGCAAACAUUGACCCUAGUCCAGAUGCUCCUCCUCCUACUUGGGAACAGCUGGAAAAUGGGCUGGUUGCUGUGCGUACAGUGGUACAUGGGCUGGUUGAUUAUAUCCAGAACCACAGCAAAAAAGGAGCAGAUCAGCAGCAGCCUCCACAGCAUAGCAAAUACAAAACAUACAUGUGUCGAGAUAUGAAGCAGAGAGGAGGAUGCCCUCGUGGGGCCAGCUGUACAUUUGCACACUCACAGGAGGAACUGGAAAAAUUUCGUAAAAUGAAUAAGCGCCUGGUUCCGAGAAGACCCUUGAGUGCCUCUUUGGGUCAACUUAAUGAGGUGGGCCUGCCUUCAGCAGCUAUCCUUCCAGAUGAAGGUGCAGUGGAUCUCCCUAGCAGAAAACCUCCUGCUCUGCCAAAUGGAAUUGUAUCAACAGGGAAUACAGUAACACAGCUUAUUCCGCGAGGGACAGACCCCAGCUAUGAUUCUAGUCUGAAACCAGGAAAAAUAGAUCAUCUGAGCAGUAGUGCUCCUGGAUCCCCUCCUGACCUGCUAGAAUCUGUUCCUAAGAGUAUUUCUGCCUUACCUGUGAAUCCACAUUCUAUACCUCCAAGGGGGCCAGCAGAUCUGCCUCCAAUGCCUGUUACCAAACCACUUCAGAUGGUACCUCGAGGUUCUCAGUUAUAUCCAGCACAACAGACGGAUGUUUAUUAUCAGGAUCCUCGAGGAGCAGCUCCGCCAUUUGAACCAGCACCUUAUCAGCAGGGUAUGUAUUAUACUCCACCACCACAAUGUGUGUCCCGCUUUGUCCGACCUCCACCAUCUGCUCCUGAACCUGCUCCUCCCUACUUGGAUCAUUAUCCACCCUACCUCCAAGAACGUGUUGUAAACUCUCAGUAUGGCACACAGCCACAGCAGUACCCACCUAUAUACCCAUCUCACUAUGAUGGCCGUCGAGUGUACCCUGCUCCGUCUUACACAAGAGAAGAGAUAUUCCGAGAAAGCCCUAUACCCAUUGAGAUUCCACCUGCAGCAGUACCAUCGUAUGUACCAGAAUCCAGAGAAAGAUACCAACAGAUCGAGAGUUACUAUCCAGUGGCUCCUCAUCCAACUCAGAUCAGACCUUCGUACCUCAGAGAACCUCCUUAUAGCCGGCUUCCUCCUCCUCCCCAGCCUCAUCCUAGUCUAGAUGAACUACAUCGCCGACGAAAGGAAAUAAUGGCCCAGCUAGAGGAAAGAAAGGUUAUCUCUCCACCUCCUUUUGCACCUUCACCAACCUUGCCUCCUACCUUUCAUCCGGAAGAAUUUUUGGAUGAAGACUUGAAGGUAGCUGGGAAAUACAAAGGAAAUGAUUAUAGCCAAUACUCUCCCUGGUCAUGUGACACCAUCGGCUCCUACAUUGGAACCAAAGAUGCAAAACCCAAAGAUGUUGUGGCAGCAGGGAGUGUGGAAAUGAUGAAUGUGGAGAGUAAAGGAAUGAGGGACCAGCGAUUAGAUCUUCAGAGAAGAGCAGCAGAAACCAGUGAUGAUGACCUCAUCCCAUUUGGAGACCGACCAACAGUGUCUCGGUUUGGUGCCAUCUCACGAACUUCCAAAACUAUAUAUCAGGGUGCUGGUCCAAUGCAGGCUAUGGCACCUCAGGGAGCUCCUACAAAAUCUAUUAACAUUUCAGAUUAUAGUCCAUAUGGAACCCACGGUGGCUGGGGAGCUUCUCCAUAUUCACCUCAUCAAAACAUACCUUCUCAGGGACACUUCAGUGAGAGGGAGAGAAUAUCUAUGUCAGAAGUGGCCAGUCAUGGAAAACCCCUUCCAUCUGCUGAGAGAGAACAGCUACGACUAGAAUUGCAGCAAUUGAACCAUCAGAUUAGCCAGCAGACCCAGCUACGUGGACUAGAGGCUGUUAGUAACAGGCUGGUGUUGCAGAGGGAGGCAAACACCCUGGCAGGCCAGUCACAGCCCCCACCACCGCCACCUCCAAAAUGGCCUGGGAUGAUCUCAAGUGAGCAGUUGAGCUUGGAACUGCACCAGGUGGAAAGGGAAAUCGGGAAGAGAACACGGGAACUGAGUAUGGAAAACCAGUGUUCUCUGGACAUGAAAAGCAAACUGAAUACAAGUAAACAAGCAGAAAAUGGACAACCAGAACCACAAAACAAGGUUCCGGCUGAGGACCUUACAUUGACAUUCAGCAGUGAUGUACCAAAUGGAUCAGCCUUGACACAAGAGAAUAUCAGCCUCCUAUCAAACAAGACCAGCUCUCUGAACCUGUCAGAGGACCCUGAGGGAGGAGGGGAUAAUAAUGACUCCCAGAGAUCAGGAGUUACUCCCAGUUCUGCUCCUUAAAAUAUGAGGAGUCCUACUUUUAUCUUCUGCUCCUAAUCAGUUUGUCGGGCAUAGGGGUAGGAGAACGCAUAACUUCUAAACUUUUUCUCUUAAGAGCGGUCAGAGAAAUCCAGGAAAUUCACCAGAGGCAAUGUGCACAAACACCACUACUAAAAACAAACCCUGCACAUAGUUCACAUUAAUGCAUUUUUUUAAUUUAAAGAAAAAGAAAAUUAGCAGUAUCUGCAAGCAAUUCAGAUUAAAUUUGUUUUUGUUCUGUGAAUGAACUUUAUUUUAAUAACUUUGGACGCCUUGGAUCCAGGGCUUUAAAAAAAAAAGAUAUUAUAUAUACACUCUGUUUGAUUAAUUGUAUGAUCUUAAUGAAGUAGGUUUUCUUGUAUUUUGGUAUUACAUACCCAGUGUAUAAUUUGUAUAAUUCCUCACCCCCAAUCCUUAUCAAUUCUCACCACCCCAUAAACUUAAAACAGACCAAAAAUGUCAGCUUUCAGAGAAUUCUGUGGUGCUUGAGAAACAGACAGUACUAGACUGAGUUAUUAGAAAAUGUGCAGCAAACCAACUUUUCCCAGAGCUGUUAUUUGGAAUUCUUUAUCCCUUUCUAGAUCACUAGCUUCAUUGGAUACGUAUAUUUUUCUUGACAUUGAAGCUUUUUGUUUGUUUGGGAGGGUUUUAUUUCUUGUUUUUAUUUUCAACUUUUCAAAUAGAAUUACCAAUUUUGAAGUCCUCAUUUUCAUAUUAAGGAUCAUUUGCAUUCUCUUAAUAUAAUCAGAAAGCUGAUUCAGUGUUUAAUUAGAUUUAAAUGUUGAUCAAGAAUUAACUGUAACUUACUAGCACUGAAAAUACAUGUUUGGUGUUUCGCCUGCGUUCAGCUCAUGGUUGGAAAUUUGAAGCAGUGCUUUUCAAAUUAAACUUUUGCUGACAUCAUAGGAUGCUAAAAAACAAGGACAAUCAACUAUGUUUUAAAACUGCAACAUUUGAUUUGAACUUAAAAUGAAUAGAGCCACAUUAUUUUAAUGGAUGUUUUGUUUUACUUGUGAACUGAUUGAGUCUUAAGGAUAGUUUAUGAAUUGAUCACUUGUUGCUCAGAAUCAUUAGUAUAAGUAGGUAGGAAAUAGUUUGAAGUCAUUUUUCAUAGACUUAACUGUCCAAUGUUGCAAAUGUUUCUUCAUGAAAAUAUUGAAAAGAGUAAGGUUUUUUUUUUUUUUAAUUCUGCUGCACAUAUUCUGAUGCCAUGUGUCUGUGCUUAAUUAACUAAGACCCUAUAAAACGUGUUUAGUGGGGACUGUUUGAUAUAGUUGCCCUCUCCAUUCCUCUAUUUGCCUGAUUUUUUUCAGUUUCCCUUUCUGUAUUUUACUACUAAAUUAGAAAGCACUGGUUAUGUAAUAAGUUACUACAUUGCUUUGGUUGAGUAAAAACAAGAGUUUAUAUUUUUCUUGUUUCUUAUUUUCUUAACCCUUAACUCCUGCUGAGGUCAUAACAACCUCAGUCUAAGCUCUGUGUCCAUCAUACUGUUAACUUAAACAAAUGGGUGGUGGGGGUGGGAAGGGUAAUACAGUCCUGCCAUUGCCUACCAGUAGGAGAGUCCAAACAGAACACUCUUUUGAGUAGCAAUUAUUUAAUUUGCCCAGUCAAGGCACCGUGUUUAUAUACUAUUUCACAUUGAAUUUGAUUAUGCCCUACAGACCUGGCUGGUCAAGGAUUUGAUAUACACAUAUUGGCUUGGGAUUCGAGCUUUCUUUUUUAUUUAAAUAAAAAUUUAUAUAUAUAUUAUAUAUAUACAUAUAUACAUAGCUAUAUCUGUAUAUAUAUUGGGUAUGUUUUAAGGAUUUUUUCGCAUGAGCGCAGCUGUUGCGAUAAAUUGACCGAUUGGGAGGUGGUAGAAGCACUGAAUGAAGGUGAGGCUUUUUUUUUUUCCAGUUUUCUUAUACAUUUGUCUUCUUUUUUUAAAAAAAAAAAAAAAAAUAUAUAUAUAUAUAUAUAUAUAUAUAUAUAUGUAUGCUUUUUCUUUUUUUUUUGGCUUUUGUUUGCUUUUUGACUUUUACUUAAAACCCUUUUACAUUUCCACUUUAAAUGCCUAUUGUUUAUUGGGAGAAGGAAAGAAACUUUUGUAUGUCUGACAGAGUCCCAAGAUUUUUCAUUUCUCUGCAUAACAGUAAAAGGCAACAUUAUUGGCCUCCAACCUUCUUUUUUUUUUUUUUUUUUUUUUUUUGGAGAGGGAGUCUGCUUCUGUUGCCCAGGCUGGAGUGCAGUGGGUUGAUCUCGGCUCGCUACAACCUCCACCUCCCGGGUUCAAGCGAUUCUCCUGCCUCAGCCUCCUGAGUAGCUGGGACUACAGGCACGCGCCACCACGUCCAGCUAAUUUUUGUACUACAACCUUCUUAUAAGCAGAUUUGGACUGAUCUUCUCCUUUGGGUAUGUCAGAUCAUCCUAAAUUUUAGAAGCAGUUGAUUCACUUUGGAAUUCAGAAUGAUUCUUGUAUUAGAAGAUAAUUUGUGGGUAUUAAUUUUUGUUUAAGUUUAAAAUAAAAGUAAAGAUUCAUUUUGGAUAUCAGUUGAAACCCCUUAGUAACUCAGUUUCUGUUAUUCUUGUUCUCAUUUCCUUUAAAUACACUUGUUCUUGGCUUUUGCCAUUUUGAUUCUGUGAAGUAGGCAGGAGCAGGGAUUAAUUUAUACAGUAUUCCUGUUCUGAACAAAACCAGAAAAGUCACUGUAUAAACUUGACUUAAAAUAGUAUCUUUCUCUUUUCAUGUAUUUUCAUUUGGGGGAAAAAAAAUCUCUUUAAUUGUAACCUGAAUUCAAGCUGUACCCCUCCAUGGUCCUACACUCUAGAGCUAAUCUGGUUGGGCAGAAAGGCAGAAGGAUGGUAUAUUGUCCCAUUGUGCCUAUAAUGUAUUUUAAAUUGGUCAUUCCACCUUACCUAAUGGAAAUUCUUGCAGCUUUCCUAGUGCUCAUCAGCGGUUUUAGGAAUUCACUAACACCCCCAAAAUUUGUUUUUUGUUUUUUGCUUUUUUUCCUUUUCCUUUUCUCUGUGAUAUCAUGAGCCUGUAAGGACAAAUGGCAUAUUUGGGCAUAACUGCUUGACUCUGUAACUACUUUUUUAAAAUCAAAAUUGAAAAGGUAUUAAUUGCUUCUGGCUUUUUAAUUUUUUUUUUUAGAGACAAAGAUGAAACCAGAUAGGAAAUACAGUUUUUAUGUUUUCUACUUACUAAAAUAUUAGUUUCUUCUAAAUAUUACUUUAUUUGUAUUUCACUAAAUUCCAAAGCAAAAAUCAGAUAUCUGAGAUGAACAAUUUUGAAUGGGUUAAGGUAGGAGUAAUAAGCAUUGUGUUCACUCAUACAUAGGUGAGGGAAUUUUAUUUAUAGCGAGAAAUAUAAAAGUAUUUUGACUUACUCUUUUUUCAAGGAGUCGCUAGGAAAGGGUAGAAGAACUGAGAAUAAGACAUCUAGAUUCCAUUUCUGGUUUAUAUGUAGCUCUUUUGCCUAAUUUAUAUAUAAUUUUGUCAUAAGAUAAGUCCAGUAACUGUCCUGUCUUAGAUAACGUACAGAGGCUGAAGUGACCAAAGAUCCAUUCCUUAUUACUUUUCUAAUUAAAAGAAGAGUUAGCUAGAUUUCUAGUAGUAGUAUUCUAGAUAUUGAUAAGACAUUAUUCCUAAUGCCAACUACAAAUAUUCAACUACUCAGAAUGUAUUUAAAAAAUUGUUUGGUACAGCAUUAAUGUUGGUGAUUCCUUUCUCCCAUCUUAUUUCCCUUCCCUUCUAUUCUUUCCCAUGUAUUUCUUUUGCCUAAAAGAAUAUUGGUAUGAUUCUCAUUUGCUACUUUGAGUAUAUAACUCCAUCAGACUUUCCAGAGUUCUUCAGGGAUGGAGCUCAAAGUUUACAUUUUUCCAUAUAUGUCUUUUUUUUUCUUGACCUUUUUCCACCCUGUAAUUUCCCCUUGACUUACCCACUGCCCUCCCCAAUCUGCAACAGUGACAGUUUGCUGCCUCAAAACAGAGCAUUCAAAUGAAUUCGCUUAGCCAAUAACUUCUGUGAAGUUGCCUUUUCUAAUGGUGUUAUUACUCAGUGAUGCACAAAUGUGGUAUUUGCCCUACUGGUAGGCAAACAAAGGUCUGGUUAAGAAUGGUAACCUGCUGUUUUCUUUAAAGGAGAGCCAAAGACUUGUGCUUUACUCUGUUUUGGUUUUGGGGGAAGUAGUAGCCAUUUUGAUCAUGAAACCUUUUAGUAUUUGUGAGUUGAUUGUACUGUGUAAGUAGAUUUAUCUAAAGUUAACUGUUAAAGUUAGCUAGCCUUAUAAAAUGUAAAAGUAAUGAAAAUUCAUCAGUUUCUCUAAGCCAGUGAAUGUCGUCUUUUGUAAUAUUGUGUAUAAGCAUUUGUGCCCACCCCAGCUUCUGCUAUCACUGUGGUCAAGUCAUGGGUCUGAGUAAAAGAAUUCUUGAGUAUGUGACUGGUGAGAAAUAACUAACUAUAGUCAGUACAUGUACAGAUUGUUAAAAUUCAAGACAAAAUACUUUCACUAAAAAAAAGGAUUCGUCUCAGUAAAGAAGUAUUCAGUUGCUGUCACUUACAUACAAAUGGUGGUGGGUAGCAGUCUCACCAUUUUUCUACUCUCUUUUUGCUCGUUUUAAAUAAUUGAGUAAAGGUUUUAUUUGUAAAAUCUAUCUGUAAAAAGCACCUGUAACGAUUUAUAUGUCAUUGAAAGGAAUGGCCCAGUUACUUUUUAGGAGAGAUUAAUAACCUACCUGGAAAUUAACUGCAGUGUUUACUUAGAUUUUUUCCCCCUAAUAAGAGUCUAAGUGUGUUAAAUUUUUAACUGAUGAUAUGGUUACAGUGUUGCAAGGUGAUCUCUUCCCCUGAAAAAUCUGCCUAUCCUUUUAAGAAAAAUUAGACCUACUAAACUAAAGCAAAUUUUACUUUCAUCAUUAGCACCUAAACAAGCAAGCAGUCUACUACUGUCAUCAUUUUACCUGAGUGCCCAUUUUGCUGAUCCACAUUCAUACCUUUCUACCUUGGACAGCUAUGAUUUUUAUAUUUAUUUGUUGCUUCAGCUCAGGUUUAUGAAAUUUUCCUGCUGAAAUGACUUAUUGGGAGUUGUAGGUUGAUUAUAGUUACUAUUAAACAUUUUCUCAAUUUAGCUUUUCUGAGCCACUUCAAGAAGAAAGCUGUUUUUGUCAAAAGGUACUAUUAAUUGUAGCAAGUAAAUCUUAAGAUUUGAAUUUUUAAGAUUUUAUUUCUGUGUUCACUAAAGAUCUUUCCACAAGUAAUAGAUUAUAAUUGAUAAGUAAUACUAGCUAUAGUGUUAAUAAAGAGUAAGACUAUCACCACCAGGAAUAAGUAACACCUUUUAAUAAUAAAUCUAUUCCUAAUAGGUAUGUUUUCAAUACUGCACUGAACAAAGUGGGUAAAGAGCCCUUUGAAAUCUUAUUGUAAUAAAGGGACUUACCUCACCACUGGAAUCCUUGUUUUCAGAGCCUCUGGAUUUUCAGCCAAACACUGAAUUUCUCCUAAACUUUAUCCCUGAAACAUCCCUAGAGAACGAACUUUAUUUUCACAAGAAAAUAAGGCACAAUAAGGGGGAAGAACUUAAACCUCAACAUAAUAUCGUGUCCAAAAAUGUGUAUUUAGAAAAAUAAAAUCCUGUGGAGUUUGUUAUCCUAAUGUUUAUUUUAUACUAGAUAAGGUGACUUGUUUUCUUGUAUUGAGGUCUUACUGUUUCAGAUUUGUUUUUGUUUCUGUUCUAACUCUAAGCAGACAGAGCUCACAAGUCUUUGGCAUCCAUUUUAGGUUGUACACUCAGAGUCAUCUUAUAACUGGAAACUGUCAGGUGGUCCCCCACCCCAGUGAGUGUAUGAAAGAGUCAAGAAAAAGAUUGGAAACAAACUAUUGGGUGAAUAAUUGGUUGCUCUAUUAUUAUUAUUAUUAUUAUUUGCCUUUUUUUAAUCACCAUUUAUUUGUGUAAUCUUUCUCCAUUGAUUGGCUGUCAUUCUUAUAAUAUCUGAACUACCCCAUAAAAUAAUUCUCUGACUUAAAGGCAUUUAGCUUUUGCUUAUCGUUUUUACAUCCUCUAUUCAACUAAGACACUGUCUUGAGAGUUAUUUUUUCCAGAUGGAUCGUUGGCCUAAAUUUUCACACUUCUCCCCUGUUCAUCCUUUUUCCUCUUCCCUGCUUCCUGGGAAUAAAAGGAACUUUUUUAAAAAAAUUAAUUAGUCCACAGGUCUCAUUAUCUUUCUUUAUGAUUAAUCUAUGACUUUUUGGUACAAGAACAAUGGAAAAAGUGAAUUAAGGUAAUGAACAAAACCUUUCACCCACUUAAACAUUUUCCAGUUUUGAGAUUCCUCUUCGUGUUUGUGGUGUCUUCCCCUUGUUACCCCUUCUGCCCUUUUUCUCUGACUAUGGUAAUUUGGUCUUUAGGCUCAUAUCAGUCUCCCCGAGACAUUCUGCAGUCAUUAUCACCUUUUUGGGUGGAUUUUAUUUUGUUUUAUUUUGUUUUUUUUAAAAAAAUAACUUUUUAACAUUGGUGCAUAUUUGCUUGGGAUAGAGCUUGUGUAAUUUACCAAUCGUAUUGAUUGUAAGUGAUUGUGCCCUGCAGAGGUAUAUUUAACAAGACAAAAAUAAUCUUGGUUAAUAAAGGAGCCCAUGAGAUUUGAGUCAGGUUGUAAGUGAAAUCACUUACACUUUUGGAUAGAAUUUAUACUCCUGCUCUUAUAAAUCAGUGGUAGACUUACCAUUUUUUAAAGUUUUCUUGCAUUUUUUUGUUUUUUUAUUGCCACAGCUCCCUAUUCUUUCUUGCCUGCCUCCACCCCCCUGUUCAGGAAAAAAAAAAAUUGAGCCUUAAAGUGACAGCUGAUUUUUUAAUUGCUGAAUUUUGUGAAAUUUUACUUUUUCCAAGUGUUUCCAACUUUAAAAAGAGAAGUGAAGACAAAUAGGUUGGAAUGGUGAAGACAAAUGGAUUGGAAUUUCACAGGCUGUGAAUAAUUCCUUAGGAUCUGGCAAACCGUGAAGUCUUAUUUGAAGACCUUAUCUCCUGAGAGUUCUUUUGGAGUAGGAAAAAGAACCCUAUUUGAAAUAGACCGUUUUUCUCUUGUUUUUAAUCUGUUUAAUAUUUCUGAUUUUUAAGCAGCUUUCAAAACAAGUGUGGUGGAAAAAAAGAAAUAGUAGUAGGAAGAUGUUUAGGGCAGCAGAACUCUGGGUCUAAAUAAGUACAUGUUCCCACUUGUUGCCGAUUUUUGAGAGUACUAGGGCCAUCUUUCUCAAUUUUGUAUUAUUUGUGUGCAUGUUUAUAUCAAAGAUGCCCAUUUUGUUAAAAUGCUAUUUCCUUUAUUACCUUGGAAACUGACUCAGCCUCAUGUUGCUCCUAAUUAGUGUUUAAGGCUCCCAUGAGUUGCAGAUAAAAUGAUUUAUUUUAACAAGUAGAAGGAGGUGAUUCACCUUUUGGAUUGUAAAUAUAUGAAAAUGUCUACAAGGUCUUUAUCUGCUUUCUGUCAGCAUUUAUAUUAAAUGAUAAAUUAAUGAGGAACGUGUGUAUUUUGUAAAUGAGUGUGUGCCAUCUUAUUCUAAUCUUGAGAUUACUUUCUUACACGUUUUUAAUGGAGGGGGCUUUUUUAGGUGAAAAAUAAAGAAAUGGCUAAUCUGCAUGAGCAAACACA